CCCAGAGCAAGCCGAUUCUCUACACACUGCCUUCCCUUCCUGUAAGACUCAUCAAAAAGGCACCCCAACCUUGCAUGGAUCUGCUGUUGGUAUUCCUUGGGGUGAAGCCAGAAGUCAGGCUUUCCACAGAGAGACGGGACUACAUGGCCACCUGGGAAGGCUAGGGAGUCAAAGGGCCUGAGGAAUGACUACUUCCCUCCACAAGGGCAUUCCCUGCCCUGCUCUGCUUCCUGGGGGCUUCAGCAAGCCUUCCUUCUAGAGCUCCUAGAACCCUCCCAUGGUCAACACAACAGCAGCCCAGACAAUGAGAUGCAAGAGGCCUGAGCUCACAGGCCAUUCAGGUCUUCUAGAUGCCUUCUUGAGGCUGCUUGUGGCCACCCACAGACACUUGUAAGGAGGAGAGAAGUCAGCCUGGCAGAGAGACUCUGAAAUGAGGGAUUAGAGGUGUUCAAGGAGCAAGAGCUUCAGCCUGAAGACAAGGGAGCAGUCCCUGAAGACGCUUCUACUGAGAGGUCUGCCAUGGCCUCUCUUGGCCUCCAACUUGUGGGCUACAUCCUAGGCCUUCUGGGGCUUUUGGGCACACUGGUUGCCAUGCUGCUCCCCAGCUGGAAAACAAGUUCUUAUGUCGGUGCCAGCAUUGUGACAGCAGUUGGCUUCUCCAAGGGCCUCUGGAUGGAAUGUGCCACACACAGCACAGGCAUCACCCAGUGUGACAUCUAUAGCACCCUUCUGGGCCUGCCCGCUGACAUCCAGGCUGCCCAGGCCAUGAUGGUGACAUCCAGUGCAAUCUCCUCCCUGGCCUGCAUUAUCUCUGUGGUGGGCAUGAGAUGCACAGUCUUCUGCCAGGAAUCCCGAGCCAAAGACAGAGUGGCGGUAGCAGGUGGAGUCUUUUUCAUCCUUGGAGGCCUCCUGGGAUUCAUUCCUGUUGCCUGGAAUCUUCAUGGGAUCCUACGGGACUUCUACUCACCACUGGUGCCUGACAGCAUGAAAUUUGAGAUUGGAGAGGCUCUUUACUUGGGCAUUAUUUCUUCCCUGUUCUCCCUGAUAGCUGGAAUCAUCCUCUGCUUUUCCUGCUCAUCCCAGAGAAAUCGCUCCAACUACUACGAUGCCUACCAAGCCCAACCUCUUGCCACAAGGAGCUCUCCAAGGCCUGGUCAACCUCCCAAAGUCAAGAGUGAGUUCAAUUCCUACAGCCUGACAGGGUAUGUGUGAAGAACCAGGGGCCAGAGCUGGGGGGUGGCUGGGUCUGUGAAAAACAGUGGACAGCACCCCGAGGGCCACAGGUGAGGGACACUACCACUGGAUCGUGUCAGAAGGUGCUGCUGAGGAUAGACUGACUUUGGCCAUUGGAUUGAGCAAAGGCAGAAAUGGGGGCUAGUGUAACAGCAUGCAGGUUGAAUUGCCAAGGAUGCUCGCCAUGCCAGCCUUUCUGUUUUCCUCACCUUGCUGCUCCCCUGCCCUAAGUCCCCAACCCUCAACUUGAAACCCCAUUCCCUUAAGCCAGGACUCAGAGGAUCCCUUUGCCCUCUGGUUUACCUGGGACUCCAUCCCCAAACCCACUAAUCACAUCCCACUGACUGACCCUCUGUGAUCAAAGACCCUCUCUCUGGCUGAGGUUGGCUCUUAGCUCAUUGCUGGGGAUGGGAAGGAGAAGCAGUGGCUUUUGUGGGCAUUGCUCUAACCUACUUCUCAAGCUUCCCUCCAAAGAAACUGAUUGGCCCUGGAACCUCCAUCCCACUCUUGUUAUGACUCCACAGUGUCCAGACUAAUUUGUGCAUGAACUGAAAUAAAACCAUCCUACGGUAUCCAGGGAACAGAAAGCAGGAUGCAGGAUGGGAGGACAGGAAGGCAGCCUGGGACAUUUAAAAAAAUAAAAAUGAAAAAAAAACCCAGAACCCAUUUCUCAGGGCACUUUCCAGAAUUCUCUCAUAUUUGUGGGCUGGGAUCAAGCCUGCAGCUUGAGGAAAGCACAAGGAAAGGAAAGAAGAUCUGGUGGAAAGCUCAGGUGGCAGCGGACUCUGACUCCACUGAGGAACUGCCUCAGAAGCUGCGAUCACAACUUUGGCUGAAGCCCCUGCCUCACUCUAGGGCACCUGACCUGGCCUCUUGCCUAAACCACAAGGCUAAGGGCUAUAGACAAUGGUUUCCUUAGGAACAGUAAACCAGUUUUUCUAGGGAUGGCCCUUGGCUGGGGGAUGACAGUGUGGGAGCUGUGGGGUACUGAGGAAGACACCAUUCCUUGACGGUGUCUAAGAAGCCAGGUGGAUGUGUGUGGUGGCUCCAGUGGGUGUUUCUACUCUGCCAGUGAGAGGCAGCCCCCUAGAAACUCUUCAGGCGUAAUGGAAAAUCAGCUCAAAUGAGAUCAGGCCCCCCCAGGGUCCACCCACAGAGCACUACAGAGCCUCUGAAAGACCAUAGCACCAAGCGAGCCCCUUCAGAUUCCCCCACUGUCCAUCGGAAGAUGCUCCAGAGUGGCUAGAGGGCAUCUAAGGGCUCCAGCAUGGCAUAUCCAUGCCCACGGUGCUGUGUCCAUGAUCUGAGUGAUAGCUGCACUGCUGCCUGGGAUUGCAGCUGAGGUGGGAGUGGAGAAUGGUUCCCAGGAAGACAGUUCCACCUCUAAGGUCCGAAAAUGUUCCCUUUACCCUGGAGUGGGAGUGAGGGGUCAUACACCAAAGGUAUUUUCCCUCACCAGUCUAGGCAUGACUGGCUUCUGAAAAAUUCCAGCACACCUCCUCGAACCUCAUUGUCAGCAGAGAGGGCCCAUCUGUUGUCUGUAACAUGCCUUUCACAUGUCCACCUUCUUGCCAUGUUCCAGCUGCUCUCCCAACCUGGAAGGCCGUCUCCCCUUAGCCAAGUCCUCCUCAGGCUUGGAGAACUUCCUCAGCGUCACCUCCUUCAUUGAGCCUUCUCUGAUCACUCCAUCCCUCUCCUACCCCUCCCUCCCCCAACCCUCAAUGUAUAAAUUGCUUCUUGAUGCUUAGCAUUCACAAUUUUUGAUUGAUCGUUAUUUGUGUGUGUGUGUCCGAUCUCACAAGUAUAUUGUAAACCCUUCGGUGGGUGGGGGCCAUAUCCUAGACCUCUCUGUAUCCCCCAGACUAUCUGUAACAGUGCCAGGCACACAGUAGGUGAUCAAUAAACACUUGUUGAUUGAG